GCAGAACGCUCCAGACGCUGAGAGGCAGGAGGCACUAGGGAUCGUCCGCAGGAUUGGGACUGAUACAGAGGCCGCCACGGAGCCCGCCGGAGCCACCGUUCCUGCUGCUGCCGCCGCUGCCCGAAUCGGAACCGUCGGGCCGCAGCCGCCGGCAAUGCCGCGAAGGAAGAGGAAUGCAGGCAGUAGUUCAGAUGGAACCGAAGAUUCCGAUUUUUCUACAGAUCUCGAGCACACAGACAGUUCAGAAAGUGAUGGCACAUCCCGACGAUCUGCUCGAGUCACCCGCUCCUCAGCCAGGCUAAGCCAGAGUUCUCAAGAUUCCAGUCCUGUUCGAAAUCUGCAGUCUUUUGGCACUGAGGAGCCUGCUUACUCUACCAGAAGAGUGACCCGUAGUCAGCAGCAGCCUACCCCAGUGACACCGAAAAAAUACCCUCUUCGGCAGACUCGUUCAUCUGGUUCAGAAACUGAGCAAGUGGUUGAUUUUUCAGAUAGAGAAACUAAAAAUACAGCUGAUCAUGAUGAGUCACCGCCUCGAACUCCAACUGGAAAUGCGCCUUCUUCUGAGUCUGACAUAGACAUCUCCAGCCCCAAUGUAUCUCACGAUGAGAGCAUUGCCAAGGACAUGUCCCUGAAGGACUCAGGCAGUGAUCUCUCUCAUCGCCCCAAGCGCCGUCGCUUCCAUGAAAGCUACAACUUCAAUAUGAAGUGUCCUACACCAGGCUGUAACUCUCUAGGACACCUUACAGGAAAACAUGAGAGACAUUUCUCCAUCUCAGGAUGCCCACUGUAUCAUAACCUCUCAGCUGACGAAUGCAAGGUGAGAGCACAGAGCCGGGAUAAGCAGAUAGAAGAAAGGAUGCUGUCUCACAGGCAAGAUGACAACAACAGGCAUGCAACCAGGCACCAGGCACCAACGGAGAGACAGCUUCGAUAUAAGGAAAAAGUGGCUGAACUCAGGAAGAAAAGAAAUUCUGGACUGAGCAAAGAACAGAAAGAGAAAUAUAUGGAACACAGACAGACCUAUGGGAACACACGGGAACCUCUUUUAGAAAACCUGACAAGCGAGUAUGACUUGGAUCUUUUCCGAAGAGCACAAGCCCGGGCUUCAGAGGAUUUGGAGAAGUUAAGGCUGCAAGGCCAAAUCACAGAGGGAAGCAACAUGAUUAAAACAAUUGCUUUUGGCCGCUAUGAGCUUGAUACCUGGUAUCAUUCUCCAUAUCCUGAAGAAUAUGCACGGCUGGGACGUCUCUAUAUGUGUGAAUUCUGUUUAAAAUAUAUGAAGAGCCAAACGAUACUCCGCCGGCACAUGGCCAAAUGUGUGUGGAAACACCCACCUGGUGAUGAGAUAUAUCGCAAAGGUUCAAUCUCUGUGUUUGAAGUGGAUGGCAAGAAAAACAAGAUCUACUGCCAAAACCUGUGCCUGUUGGCCAAACUUUUUCUGGACCACAAGACAUUAUAUUAUGAUGUGGAGCCCUUCCUGUUCUAUGUUAUGACAGAGGCGGACAACACUGGCUGUCACCUGAUUGGAUAUUUUUCUAAGGAAAAGAAUUCAUUCCUCAACUACAACGUCUCCUGUAUCCUUACUAUGCCUCAGUACAUGAGACAGGGCUAUGGCAAGAUGCUUAUUGAUUUCAGUUAUUUGCUUUCCAAAGUCGAAGAAAAAGUUGGCUCCCCAGAACGUCCACUCUCAGAUCUGGGGCUUAUAAGCUAUCGCAGUUACUGGAAAGAAGUACUUCUCCGCUACCUGCAUAAUUUUCAAGGCAAAGAGAUUUCUAUCAAAGAAAUCAGUCAGGAGACGGCUGUGAAUCCUGUGGACAUUGUCAGCACUCUGCAAGCCCUUCAGAUGCUCAAAUACUGGAAGGGAAAACACCUAGUUUUAAAGAGACAGGACCUGAUUGAUGAGUGGAUAGCCAAAGAGGCCAAAAGGUCCAACUCCAAUAAAACCAUGGAUCCCAGCUGCUUAAAAUGGACCCCUCCCAAGGGCACUUAAAGUGACCUGUCAUUCCGAGCCAGCGAACCCCAGCAGUAGGAAUCCGUACCCUAGGGAUCUGUCUGUCAUUUCUCUGUUGCUCUUGUGAUUGGCAAGUACAGUAUCCUUUGGGAAGGCCAUCCCCCUCAGGACUGUCCUGGCUCCGACCUUUGUGUACACUGCAGACGCUGGUUCUGAGGAACUGUUGUUUCGGCCUCAGUGAGGUUGCCUGGAUGGGAUCUGUAUUAGACUUGAGUGCAGGUCUCUCAGCACUGACCCAAGGAGUUCUGUUAUGGUACUGUACCUGUCCAGUCACUGGUUCUCUCCUCAUGUCCUCUCGCCCCAUGAGGUUGUGUUGUGUCUUCUAAGCGUGGUACUAGUGCUUGCCACCUGGUCACCAGACCUCCAAAUAUGGCUGCCACCACCAGGACCUUUCCAGUUACUCCUUAUAUGUGUGUUCUAUGGAGGGGCAGGGAAAAGGUGGCACUUGUGAGUGUGUGUGGAUUGGCAGGGGGUCCAUUCACUUUGGGUUCCAUCUUGCUUUAAAUUUCUUCAUUUUGAUUAAGAGACCUCUUUUUGAUCUGUAUUGGGCUAACCAGAGCCAAAUACUUUUGAAGAGUUUCCCAGGGACUAGUCAUGGUAAUAGCAUAUAAUUGAUCUGAAUGAGAUGGAGAGAAGAAUGAAGGGGUGGUGGUUCUGGGUUUGAUUUGAGUUCACCUGUGGGCAGUGGGCAGUGGGCAGUGUCUUGGUGAAAGGGAACGGAUACUACUUUUUGCCUCACCGUAAAGUACUCACUAGUAAAUAUUUCCUUCUCUCUUUACUCCCACUUUUUACGUUUGCAGGUGCCAAAGUAAUGUCCACUUUUCCCUUUCAUGCUGCAUAUUAACUGGUUAAUUAUACUGCAGAAACCUUUUCACCUCCACUAGUCUGAUACAGUACAUCUGUACUUCCAUAUACCUUGCACUGAUUUUGUCUGAGUGCCCUGGGAGAAGUAGAAAAUGAUUGAAAGUGACUUCCGUAUCUCAGCCCAUGACUCAGCAAGGCAGAAUGGCCACCCCUGCCAAAGUUUGCUUCUCUUUUCAACAGUGCCUCACCCUCCCUCUAGGAUUAAAGUGCUUCUGCCCUUCCACGAACUCCUCCUCCAUUUCCUUUUUGGGAUUUGUCACCAUCCUUCUAUUCUCUGGUCUUCUAUUUUUGGUGUUGUUCAAGUGAAGGAAGAGAUGUUCCCUCUAAUUUCUCUCUAGCCCAUUAUAACCUGCUAUCUUGGGGCAACUUUUGAUGUAUGACAUGUCACCCUUCCCAACUUGGUCUCCUCCAACAUGCUGUCUUCAUGUGGAGCCCUCACCACAAUCCCUGACUCCGGUCAUUUGUGCCUUUCUCUUGUCAUCUCUGUACACUACUUAUAUUCACUGUGGGUUGGGGGAGCUAAUUUUAAGCAUGUUCAGUGGCAGCUCCCCUCCAGUUUCAGUGUCACUGUUAAAAUUUAUCAAAAAGCAACUUCACUAGGGGUUUUCUUAAGGGAUAAAGGCCUUUUACAGAAGCUAAACCCUUCCCCACAUGUGGUAGAAUGUGCUCUUCUAUAUCUACUCCUCAAUAAAGCAUGUUCUCUGCUCAAGUCUGUUUCAUCUGGGGGCUCUCAUUUAUAUAUGAAAAUGAUGCACACGAUCUGCUACUAAUAGUAAAUGCACUUGGGAUUUGCUUUCCCUAGCAGUAAACUGUUGAGGGAUGUGGUUUGUGGCUAUGGAAUGUUUUUCCCUGUGAUACAGGCUGUCUGUAAAGAUCAAGGGAGUGCUCACUCUGAACUUCUCUAGAUGGUGGCACAAAUUUGAUCUGCCUCACUUUGGUUCCAGCUAAUCAGUAUACGUAGCAAUGAUUAGUCAGUAUUACCCAUUCUUUCACUAAGUGCCAUUUUCCACUGAUUUUAGGGGCAAAGGAACCAAUAGGAAAUUAGGAUAUAUGGGGGUACAGUUGAUGCCUGUAGGAGAUGGGAACAGACAUUCCUUCUCAUCUCCAAGCUCAUUCACCAGUAUUGAGCAGUGUCACCUCUAAUUAUUGACUCUCUCGCAGGUUGAAAUUAUUCUUUUUGAAAAUAGCUGCAUUUUCAUGUAAGAUAUACCCAGCACAGGAAAAGGGUGGCUGAGCACUAACCUCCGUAUGGUGGAAAGGAGGAGGCUGGGAAUUGUAUGUGCUGGAAUGGUUUCACUCACUGUGACCAGUAGUGGUGAGAACCCAUACAGUUGAAGUUUUUUGCACAGUCCUGAUCCCAGGUCUCCACUCGCUUUGCCAUCCCACUUUACUCCCUAAAAAUAAAAGGAUUUAUUAUCUCAUUUAAACCCCCACAGGUGUGGAAACAGAGUUUCACUUGCCUUGGCAACUUUGCAUGAGACUAUCCCAUUUCAUUCCGUUUUUUUUUUUUUGAGUCAGAGUCUGGCUCUGUUGCCCAGGUUGGAGUGCAGUGGCGCAGUUUUGGCUCACAACCUCUGCCUCCCGGGUUCAAGUGAUUCUUCUGUCUCAGCCUUCCGAAUAGCUGGGAUUACAGGUGCCUGUCACCAUGCCCAGCUAAUUUUUGUAUUUUUAGUAGAGACAGGGUUUCGUCAUGUUGGUCAGGCUGAUCUCGAACUCCUGACCUCAGGUGAUCCGCCCACCUUGGCCUCCCAAAGUGCUGGGAUUACAGGCGUGAGCCACUGCACCCGACCUAUUUUUUUUUUUUUUUUUUUUUUUUUUUUUAAAAAAAGACAGUCUCACUCUAUCAUCCAGUCCGGAAUGCAGUGGCAUGAUCUCAGCUCACUGCAAUGUCUGCCUCCUGGAUUCCAGUGAUUCUCCUGCCUCAGCCUCUCAAGUAGCUGGGAUUACAGGUGCAGGCCACCUGGCUAAUUUUUGUAUGUUUAGUAGAGACAGGGUUUUGCCAUGUUGGCCAGGCCAGUCUCAAACUCUUGACCUCAAGUGAUCACCCGCCUCAUCCUCCCAAAGUGCUGGGAUUACAGCCGUGAGCCUCUGCACCCAGCUUUUAACUCCCUCUUAUCUGCAUAACAGAAGCUUAGCUGCUUAAGCUCCUUUAUUAGAAGAGCAAAAGUCUGAAAUUAUUCCUGAAACCUGCUCAAUGGAAGUACCUACUCUAUUGGUUGCUUCCCAUAUGGUUGUCACUGUACCUUCAUACUGCCUCAUUUGACCCUCAUAUUAGCCCUGUACAGUAGAUGGGUACACUGGUUUGCCAAAGGAGACCUGGAAUCCAAGGUGGAAGUAAGCAGCAAAGCCAGAAACUUCAAUUCUGGUCUGUCUACCUUGAUAGCCUGCACCCUCCCCUCUACCGUUUUCUUCCACUAUUUUUGAUUCCUUAAUGAUGAAUCAUCCUCUCCCUUCUAGUUGGAUUUGUUUCUAAUGGCUUCCAUUACAAGGAUAAUAAUGAAACUGGUGAAAACUUUCAGGCAAAAGGAUUUUCUUUUUAUAUUUUUUCUUAUUAUUUUUUAAUUAUUAACCAAAUUAACUCAUUACAGUAAAAAGGACUGAUUUUUAAGCCAGCUGUGAUAGCUCUGUAAUAGUCUGUAAUCUCAGCACUUUGGGAGGCCAAGGCGGGCAGAUCGCUUGAGUCCAGGAAUUCGAGACUAGCCUGGGCAGCAUGGUGAAACCCCAGCUCUACAAAAAAUAGAAAAAUCAGACGUGGGCACAUGCCUGUAGUCUCAGCUACUUGGGAGGCUGAGGCACGAGAAUCGCCUGAACCUGGGAGGCAGAAGUUGCAAUGAGCUGAGAUGAUGCCACUGCACUCCAGCCUGGGUGACAGAGUGAGACCCUGUCUCAAAAACAAAAAACAGAAUUGAUUGAUGUUAGUUGGCUUUAGAAGCAGCAAGUUUAGGGGGCUACAGAGCUAAACCAGGAAGCAAAAGAUGUGCCUCAUUCUGGCAUUGUUUCUGAUUUAGGAAUAAACUGUUCAGUAAGCACUGUCCCUUUACUUCCAUGGUUUUCUUCAUUCCUCACCACAGCACAGUAAGGUGGAUAUUAUAGUCUUCUUCUAGAUGAAAAAUUGAGGCUCAUAGUGGUCUUGCUGCUGUGUCAUAGCAAUAGAAUGAGAGAGCCUUGCUUCCCUGAGUCCAAAUCCCAUACUUUUGGCAUUGUUAUGAGGUCUGGUCACCUGAUGCUUCCAUGCUAUUUUCCCAUUUCUUAUCUGGGGAUAAUGAGUCAUAUUAAGUAAUUUUUUUUUUUGAGACGGAGUUUCGUUCUGUCACCCAGGCUGGAGUGCAGUGGUGCGAUCUUGGCUCACUGCAAGCUCUGCCUCCCGGGUUCAUGCCAUUCUUCUGCUUCAGUCUCCCGAGUAGCUGGGACUACAGGUGCCCACCACCACGCCCAGCUAAUUUUUUGUAUUUUUAGUAGAAUGAGGUUUCACCGUGUUAGCCAGGAUGAUCUCGAUCUCCUGACCUCGUGAUCCACUCGCCUCAGCCUCCCAAAGUGCUGGGAUUACAGGCGUGAGCCAUUGCACCCAGCCAUUUUUUUUUUUUUUAAGACGACGUCUCACUCUGUCACCUAUGCUGGAGUGCAGUGGCGUGAUCUAGGCUCAUUGCAACCUCUGCCUCCCAGGUUCAAGCGAUUUUCCUGCCUCAGCCUCCCAAGUAGCUGGGAUUACAGGUGCCCACCACCUCGCCUGGCUAAUUUUUGUAUUUUUAGUAGAGAUGAGGUUUUGCCCUGUUGGCUAGGUUGGUCUUGAACUCCUGACCUCAGGUGAUCCACUCACCUCAGCCUCCCAAAGUGCUGGGAUUACAGGCAGGAGCCACUGCGCCCAGCCAAGUAACUUUUAACAGUGUGGUAUAACCUUUAAAUGACAAGGUGAUGCUUUUGACUUGUCCUCAACUUUGAUUUGUACUGAUUUGUCCCUAUAGUUCUGGGUGGGGUGGGUCAAAACAAAGUCUCGAGCUGUACCAGGAUCAAGCAGCACAGCUCAGCCAUGAUCCUUUUACCACUUUUUUCUUCUGUCCUUGAGACUCUAAUUAAAGCACUGGAUUUUUAAAAAUCACCCUUGUAAAUAUGCACACAUUUGUCUAUAGUUGAGGAAAUUGUGCCGUUGAAGUCCAUUCUUGGACAUGGAGUUAAGAAACCCUGGUUUGAGAAAAAGCCCCAGUGAGACAGCAGGAAUCCUUUUACCAUACAACCCUCAACUAGUUUAGUGUGCUCAAGCUCAAAUAACCAAUCCCAUCAAGUGAAAAGAAUGGCAGCAGGGAGAAGGCCUGGCUCACUGAGGCUCUCAGCAUUAGUUUCCUCUACCUCUUGUGUCUCACAGGUGCACAUAUGUACAGCAUAUCAAAGUGUUGAAUGUCAUGAGAAUAAAAUAUGAAAACUACUUUGCUGAAUGAUAGUAUGUGAUGUGUGCUAGGACUUCUAGAAGCCACCCUUUGCUUUGCUGUUCAUUGGGAUCAUGGAAUCGGACCUCAGCUGGUUUUGCCUCAGCACUUUCUUUCACAAAAUUAUGUGUGACUGCCUCCUCCAGACUGUUUCCUGCUGAUAGGGGCAGUUUAAUAGCCUUCUUCCUGUGUGGUAUCUGCAACAAAAUCCCAAUGAAUGUCACCAAGAAGGAAACAAAGGAUUGCCCAGCGAUGAGAAAUGUCCCUGGUGCCAAAACAUCAGUUUGCCCCUAACCUCUUGUGCAAUACCUUUAAGUCCAGGUCAUGUUGUUACCAUUUGGGGGUUUGCGGAUUUGUUUACUUGUGCCCAAGAAUGGAGAAAAUAACCUGUACUAUUGUACAACUCUGGCUCCAUGGCUCCUCACAAAUGUUCCAUGUGAGAUAUAAACAUCUUUAUCCUCGACAAGUCAUGUUCAUUCCAAGAAACCAGUCUUUGUUCUUAAUUGGACAUUUGUUUCUGCAAACAGCUUACCAUACAUUCAAUUCCAAAGUUAUCAGAAACCUACACUCUUAUCUCACAAAUUUAGAGGUGUGGUAGAUCAUCUCCAAAGAUGGCCACCAACAGUUGCUCUCAUCCUCUGUGCACGUGCUAUUUCCAAUAAGGUCUAUUUUUUUCUACAGUGAGGGCUGAACUUGUGACUUGUUUUGACUAAUAGGAUAUGGAAGUGAUAUUUUGGCAGCUUCCACUUUUGCUCUUGAAAAUAAGCUGACACGUUUCCAAACGAGAAGCUUGGGCUAAAUUACUGAAUGGUGAGAGACGAUGCAUAGGAGAACCAAGGUGCUCUAGUCACAGCACUAAAAGCCCAGACUUGUGUCUCUUGAAGGUUUCAACCCCGCCAGACUCCCAGCUGAACGCACCCUCAUGAGUGGCCCUUGCUGGUACCACAUGACACUAAAGACAUCUAGCUGAGUCCUGUUAACCCAGAGAAUUAUGAGAAUACUGUUUUAACCACACGUUUUGGAAUGGUUUGAUACAUGGCAAUGGAGAAGUGAAACAAGGGGACUUCGGAAACUAAAGGGCUGGAAUUCAGUUUGCCUUGUAGGUUGAUUGGAAGCCAGAUGUGCCUAGAGGAAGGCUACCACCUUGUGCAAUUCCAGGGGACACUGUUUAUGUUCCGUGUAAAUGGCAGCCUCAGUUCACCUCAUUUGGUUAUUUAUCGUGUCUUCGCUGUCAGUCAAAUUGCUUCUGAGAUAACUGGCUGGCCUUGGAAUUCUUAGCCACCUCCUUAAGCGGAUCAGGAAAACUGAAGAAUAUCCUUCUGUAUGUAUGUAUGUAUUUAUUGAUUGAUCGAUUUAUGAGACAGGGUCUCCUUCUGUCACCCAGGCUGGAGUGCAGUGGUACGAUCACGGCUCACUGCUGCGUCGCCUUCCCAGGCUCCAGCUAUCCUCCCACCUCAACCUCCAGAGUAGUUGAGACCACAGGCGUGCACUACCACGCCCGGCUACCUUUUUGUAUUUUCAGUAGAGACGAGGUUUCGCCGUGUUGCCCAGGCUGGUUCAAGCGGAGCUCAAGCAAUCAGCCUGCCUCGGCCUCCCAAAGUGUUGGGAUUACAGGCAUGAGCCGCUGCGCCCAACCUUCUUCUGCUGUCGAGAUACUGCUCAUCACCUGCCUGCUCCAGAAUUCAUGUGGCUUCUCAUUGCUCAAUGGAUUAAGUUCAUGUUUAUCCUGGCUUUCAAGUCUUUCCGUAAGCUGACUCAACCUACAUAGCUUUCAUCAUUCCCUUACACAUAACCUCAACGUGCAACAGGAUUAGUCUAUUAUUCCCUUUCUUGUGUUUACUGAGAAAGCCUCCACUUCAACGUUCCAUGAAGUGUGUUCCAUUAAAUACCAAAGUAUAGGCAAAAAGUUCUGUGGUCAAAUAAAUUUGGAAAACACAGAGUGUUUCCAAAGUUAGUAUCAGGCCAGGCAUGGUGGGAGGAUCACUUGAGCCCAGGAGUUCGAGACCAGCCUGGGCAACAUAGGGAGACCCAAUCCCUACAAAAAAAUUAGUUGGGCAUGGUGGUGUGCACCCGUAGUGCCAGCUACUCAGGAGGCUGAGGUAGGAGGAUCACCUGAGCCCAGGAAGUCAAGGCUGUGGUCAGCUGAGAUCCCACCAGUGUGCUCCAGCCUGGGUGACAGAGCAAGACCCUGUCUCAAAAAAUAAAAAAAUAAAGAUAA